GCGGCCGCACCCCCCGGCCGGGCCGUGCUUCUGCCCCUACAAGGUUUGGGCCGAGGUGGGGGAGGGUCCUGGUUGCCGGCCCCGCCCGGUCCCUCCCCGCCUUUUAGGCGCCCGCGUGGCCGGGACGUCCCAGUCCCGCUCCGUCCUCCUCGCCUGCCACCGGUGCACCCAGUCCGCUCACCCAGCCCAGUCCGUCCGGUCCUCACCGCCUGCCGGCCGGCCCACCCCCCACCGCAGCCAUGGACGCCAUCAAGAAGAAGAUGCAGAUGCUGAAGCUGGACAAGGAGAACGCCAUCGACCGCGCCGAGCAGGCCGAAGCCGACAAGAAGCAAGCUGAGGACCGCUGCAAGCAGCUGGAGGAGGAGCAGCAGGCCCUCCAGAAGAAGCUGAAGGGGACAGAGGAUGAGGUGGAAAAGUAUUCUGAAUCCGUGAAGGAGGCCCAGGAGAAACUGGAGCAGGCCGAGAAGAAGGCCACUGAUGCUGAGGCAGAUGUGGCCUCCCUGAACCGCCGCAUUCAGCUGGUUGAGGAGGAGCUGGACCGGGCCCAGGAGCGCCUGGCUACAGCCCUGCAGAAGCUGGAGGAGGCCGAGAAGGCGGCUGAUGAGAGCGAGAGAGGAAUGAAGGUCAUCGAAAACCGGGCCAUGAAGGAUGAGGAGAAGAUGGAACUGCAGGAGAUGCAGCUGAAGGAGGCCAAGCACAUCGCUGAGGAUUCAGACCGCAAAUAUGAAGAGGUGGCCAGGAAGCUGGUGAUCCUGGAAGGAGAGCUGGAGCGCUCGGAGGAGAGGGCUGAGGUGGCCGAGAGCCGAGCCAGACAGCUGGAGGAGGAACUUCGAACCAUGGACCAGGCCCUCAAGUCCCUGAUGGCCUCAGAGGAGGAGGUAGUGACCCCUCUGAACCUUUCUGGGCAAUGGCGCCUUCUCUCAGCUCACCUUCCCUCCGUCUCAGCACCGCAGGCUGCUCUUUCUCAGCUGCUGGGGAUCAGGAAGGGCCUGGGGCUUCUGAGCCCUGCCUGCUGUCACUCUCACAACUUUGCUCUUCUCUUCUCUCCUCCACCCGUCCCCUGCUGUGCCAUCUCCACUGUCUGGCUUCGCUGUGCCCUCACACCCUGCCCCCCCCGCCACACACCCCCUGCAGUAAAUGUGGGGACCUAGAGGAGGAGCUGAAAAUUGUUACCAACAACUUGAAAUCCCUGGAGGCCCAGGCGGACAAG